CUCUCUUCCCCCCGCCCUGCCUUCCCUUGCACCCUCCUUCUUCCCUCCGCCCGGGAGCUCUCCCUGGUCCCCGGCGCCGCCUCCUUCCCUCCCGGCUCCCCGCUCCCCGCUCCCGUGGCUGCCGCCGCCCCGGGGAAGAAGAGACAGGGGUGGGGUUUGGGGGAAGCGAGAGAGGAGGGGAGAGACCCUGGCCAGGCUGGAGCCUGGAUUCGAGGGGAGGAGGGACGGGAGGAGGAGAAAGGUGGAGGAGAAGGGAGGGGGGAGCGGGGAGGAGCGGCC